AAUUGGAGCCCCUGGUGAGGUUACGCGUGCCAUGAGAACCCACUCUACACCACGACGCUGGUGCCUCAGUGUUGGCCAAACUCUGGAGUCACUGACUGGUUUGACUUUCAUACGGUGAAUAUGCAUUUGGUCUGUACUGAUCAUGGAAUAAACACAUCUCUCUUUUUUUAAUGCUGGCGUCUCCCUGACAUUUCUUUGUGAACCAACUGUUGCCUAGGCUAGGCCCAGGGGACCCCCUGGACCCCAGACCACCUCUGUACAGGAACUACUGCCAGGGAUUACCUAGCCCCUCUCCUGUGACCUGUCCCUGUCUGCCCUGGGCGGGAGCCACGCAGACUCAUAGCAACCACCCCAAGCUGAAGCUGUGACGCAGAGCCCGGUACCCAUCCUUGUGGACCCUGGCUGAGGUGGAGGGUGUGCUCUAGCAGAACCCUGGCCAGACUCCAGACAGUAUUCUUCCCCUCCACCCUACUCCAUCCUGUCCCCCCUACUCCAUCCUGUCCCCCCACUCACCAAAGGACUUGGGCCACUUCUCCCACCUUGCCUGCCUCAACCUAACUCCUCCUUUCAUUUAAGCUCAGGGUUAACCAGAUACUCUUAGAUAUAAGUCUACAUCCCCCAAAAUAGGAUCCUCACCCCCCAUGCACAUACACACACAUUCCUGUCCAAGAAAGCCCACAGGUGGCUGCUCUGCCUGUGUGUCCACUUGUGUAUGUACAUGCCCCAGCCACAAGGCACGGGUGACGCCCAAGAAGAGCCCCUAAGAUGUAAGAUACAAGUAUAUAAUUUAUAUGUAUGCAGAGACAAACUGAUUGAAACAUUUCUAGCACUGUUUAUUCUCCUACAUCCCCUCUUUUUGACCUGAAAGGUCCUUUAUUGUCUUUGGAUCUGCCAAACCUCCCUGUGAGGGUGUGGUUCAGGCAUCCAGCCAGAGGUCCCCCCACUUCUUCGAUGUCCAUGCCCACUCAGGCACUUUCUCAUAUACCACUGUGCCACUUCAAGUGUGACGUAUUUAGGUUCUUUGGGGUUUCUUCCAUCUCAUCCCACCCACUCAUUUUUGUUCCUUGUUUUGUUCAGACACUUCCCCAGCCUGGGUCCAACUGCUGAGCUGGAUAGUUUUCUCUGCAGCUUCCUGCUGAAGAUUUAACUCAGCCAUGGCCUUCUCCACACCUCCCUGAUGGGUGUCUCUCUACCUGGGUUGUAAUUAGAACUGGGAUCUAUUUAAUUUCUCCAGCCAUUUCCCAACCCUUCCCACAGUACUAGAAAUCUUAGUCCUAUACCAGAGUAAGAGGUGUGUACAAGCCCCCACUGUACUGUAUGCACGGAUCGCUUGGCCAAUAAUUAUGUCAGUGAAUCUGAGACUUGUAUUAAACACUUUAGACAUUUGUAGAAGGGAAUUCGUAGACUUUUCACUUACAUACGAAAGGUUUUUUUUUUUUUUUGUGCAGUUCUCAUUGCAAAAAUAAACAUUUGUACUGAGUAUAAAGUUACUCUCCUGUGAUGGCUGCUUUUUGUUUGAGGGUAGACUUGGGAGAAGCGGGGAGAUGAGGGCGGGGGGUCAGUGAUGUGUAGGAGAGGAAGAAGGGAGGUUCCCCAGACACCCACCACCCAUGCGUCCAGAUUAGCGGAGUCGGUUGGGAGAGAUCCUGGGAACAUCAAAUUGUGAGAUAAUUGAUUUAAUGGAAGGUGUAAAAGAAAAAGCUGCCAGGCACGGUGGCUCACAUCUGUAAUCCCAGCACUUUUGGGAGGCCGGGGUGGGAGGAUCGCUUGAGGUCAGGAGUUAAGAGACUAGCCUGGCCAACAUGGUGAAACUCCCAUCUCUACUGAAAAAUACAAAAAAUUAGCGGGGCGCGGUAGCACACACCUGUAGUCCCGGCUACUCCGGAGGCUGAGGCAGGAGAAUUGCUUGAACACUGGAGGCGGAGGUUGCGGUGAGCCGAGAUCACACCACUGCAUUCCAGCUUGGGUGAUAUGGUGAGACUCCCAUCUCAAAAAAAACAAAAACAAAAAAACCCCCAAAGCUUUGAUGUAGGCUAAUCACACAACAAAAGAAAGGUAGUGGUUAAGUAGUCCAGGGAGAACAAAAGUUUGUACACUAUGGGCAAUGUAAUCAUAGUGGUCUAUUCGGCUCUUGAGAUGCAUUGUUCACUGAGGCAGAACAUAAACCACUAUUCACCUUUAAGUGGCAACUUCAUGGACUUAGUUAUGGUCCCAGGACAGUAUAAUGUUUAGCAGCCUUGACAGUACAAAGGUAUAUGGAUAAAAGUGGGAGGUGGAAAGGGGCAAGAGGUGACAAGUGGAGUGUUUUUAAAGGAAACUAACAGGGAAACAAAAAACGGCACGUCCGGGGUAGUGAUGUGAGCAAGUCAGUGGCUGAUGUCAUACAUUGGUUAAGUCAAGAAAUAAAGGUCAGGCACGGUGGCUUGCAUCUGUAAUCCCACUUUGGGAGGUGGAGGCUUGAGGAUUGCUUGAGGCCAGGAGUUUGAGACCAGCCUGGACAAUAUAGCAAGUCGUCUCUCUGAAAAGUUUUUGAAAAAUUAGCUGAGUGUGGUGGCACAGGCCUGUAGUCCCAACUACAGGUUGUAGUGCUUGAGCCCAGGAGUUCGAGGCUGCAGUGAGCUAUGAUCGAAACUCCAUCUGAAAAAAAAAGAAAAAGCUAAAAACGUUCCAGUGGCUGCUUCCGGGAGGAAGGGGAGGUGUAGCCACAGAUCGCUGCCUUUUUCCCUACAUCUUUGCGGAUGGCUAUUUUACAAGAUGUAUGUCUUCAGGCAAAUGACUUCAUCCUCGAAUUUCAGGUUCAUGAUCUAUACUACAGGAAUGUGAUUAUGCUACUUAGACUUAAUAGGGUUGCUCUAUGGUUAAGUGAUGGCUGUCCCUAAAAUGUUCAAGGAUAUCGGGAGAAGGUUGCAAAAUAGGAGGAAGAAGCUGGCUGCUUUUUUUUUUUUUUUUGAGACGGAGUCUCGCUCUGUCGCCCUGGCUGGAGUGCAGUGGCGCAAUCUCAGCUCACUGCAACCUCCGCCUCCUGGGUUCACGCCGUUCUCCUGCCUCAGCCUCCCUAGUAGCUGGGACUACAGGCGCCCGCCACCACGCCUGGCUAAUUUUUUGUAUUUUUAGUAGAGACAGGGUUUCACCAUGUUAGGAUGGUCUCGAUCUCCUGACCUCGUGAUCCGCCCGCCUCGGCCUCCCAAAGUGCUGGGAUUACAGGCGUGAGCCACCGCGCCUGGCCAGAAGCUGGCUUCUUGCAGGGACAGCAGGGCCGCAAGGCUCUGUGACUCUAGGCCCCAUCACACCCGGCCCUGUCCCACUUCCUCUUUCGGCCAGAACCCCAGAACUCCAGUCAUUCAUAGGCCGGGUCCUCCUCGGGGGAACCAGGCCUGCCCCCUAGGAAUCAGGGUAUCCACGCCUCCUCGGCCCGCUCUCGGAGCCUGGGCCUCAACACCUGCAGAUUGGCUCCCGGGCCAGGACCUGUCGCUUGAACAUCAGUGGCCGCCGCCGUCCAAUCACAGACGUACAGGGGCGGGCUGGCGGGCCUGUUGGGCCAGCAGGAGGACGGCGCCGGGCCGAGGCCGCUGGACCCGCCGUUGGAACCACAGCUGGGUGAAGUCAGUGCUGCUAGGUCUUUGGAGCCAGACCGAAGGGAGGGUCGCGCGCCCCUGGGCCGCACCUACUCUGCAUAUGCCCCGCCCCUCACUCCAGGUGUCGCCCACUUAACUGAAGAUCCAGGAUCCCCUCCUUAAGGUGCCCCUGGCCGGCAGCGCCGCCGUGGUCCCGGAGCGCGGCGACAUGCCGGAGCUGGUGGUGACCGCGCUGCUGGCGCCGUCGCGCCUGUCGCUGAAGCUGCUGCGCGCCUUCAUGUGGAGCCUGGUGUUCUCGGUGGCGCUGGUGGCCGCGGCGGUCUACGGCUGCAUAGCGCUCACGCACGUGCUGUGCCGGCCCCGGCGCGGCUGCUGCGGGCGCCGUCGGAGCGCGUCCCCCGCCUGCCUGAGCGACCCCUCGCUGGGUGAGCACGGUUUCCUGAACCUCAAGAGCUCGGGCCUGCGUCUGCACUAUGUCUCGGCUGGACGAGGUAACGGACCCCUCAUGCUGUUUCUGCACGGCUUCCCUGAGAACUGGUUCUCCUGGCGUUACCAGCUCCGGGAGUUCCAGAGCCGCUUCCAUGUUGUGGCUGUGGACUUGCGAGGCUAUGGCCCCUCGGAUGCACCUCGGGAUGUGGACUGCUACACAAUCGACCUGCUGCUGGUGGACAUCAAAGAUGUCAUCCUAGGCCUGGGUUACUCGAAGUGCAUCCUUGUGGCCCAUGACUGGGGUGCCCUCCUUGCCUGGCAUUUCUCCAUCUACUACCCAUCCCUGGUCGAGCGGAUGGUUGUGGUCAGUGGUGCCCCCAUGUCGGUGUACCAAGACUAUUCCCUGCACCACAUCAGCCAGUUCUUCCGUUCCCACUACAUGUUCCUGUUCCAGCUGCCCUGGCUGCCCGAGAAGCUGCUGUCUAUGUCUGACUUUCAGAUUCUGAAGACCACCCUCACCCACCGCAAGACAGGCAUCCCAUGCUUGACCCCCAGCGAGCUCGAGGCCUUCCUUUAUAACUUCUCACAGCCUGGUGGCCUCACUGGGCCCCUCAACUACUACCGAAACCUCUUCAGGAACUUCCCCCUGGAACCCCAGGAGCUGACCACACCCACAUUGCUGCUGUGGGGGGAGAAGGACACUUACUUGGAGCUGGGGCUGGUGGAAGCCAUCGGCAGCCGCUUUGUGCCGGGCCGCUUGGAGGCCCACAUCCUGCCAGGCAUAGGGCAUUGGAUCCCACAGAGCAACCCCCAGGAGAUGCACCAGUACAUGUGGGCCUUCUUGCAAGACCUGCUGGACUAGUGGUCCUUGCUGGCCUGCCCAGGAGGCAUGGAUACUCAGGAAGGAACACACACCCAUUAUCUGUGUGUGCCUGGGAGUCCAUACAAUGUCCAUACAUGGGUGAACUCUUGAAUCGCUCAUAGGCAUGGGACUCCUGGAUCCCACACAAGCGCACCUAUGGGUGCCUCGGGACACACCAACCCCUAUACUCACACACAGGCAUGGAUGCAUGUGUGUGUAACAAACACUUUGACCCUGGGAACUGGGUAUACCUCUCUUCCAGUGGAGCCAGAUGCCGAGACCGAGUGUCCCACCUCCUCCCUUCCUGGGGCCUCACUCUGCGCUUUGCCAAAGUCGCUUCUCUGCCAUAGCUGCACAGACCUUAAACCCUGACCUUCCUGUCCCUGCCUUCGACCUCCUGCCUGGGUCUUCAGCUCAGUGCUACUCUGAAUACAAUACUGCUGACCACAUUUGGCUACUUCAGCUUAAAUGUAUGUUAAUUGAAAUGAAAUACAAUGAAAAUGCAGUGCUCAGUCCCA